CCUUGAGAACUGCUGACGUGCCUCGGGCUCUUUCUACGCUACAGUCUGCCUGCAGGCUGUGAGGCGUCGUUCGGACGUGUGCGCGGCUCAGGGUUGUUUACACCGCGGGGGACUGCGGGUCGCCCCACACCCGCGCUCAGUGCUGCGCCGGCAGCCACGCGUCGGCCACAUGCCCGCCUGUGCUUGUGAUUCCUGUGCCUGCUGCCUUGAUUUCCCUCUGACAUCCGAUGGUUUUUGCCUAACCAGGCCUGUUUUCUUUCUUCAGGACUGCUACAGGGUGCCCAGCUACAACCUUGUUUCUGUGUUUAGGUUUAGGGGUGCCCCUAGAGUGUGAUGAUGACCAUCUACUUGGCCUCCUUGUCGACAUAUUUAUAACGGGUGGUUUUGGAUUUCCUUGAUUUCCCAGUAAUCAUUGCCACAAACCUUCGAGAUGCAUUCACAGAUUGAAAUACAGUAUACAAAUAACUAUUAUAGAAGGUGAAGAUGGUAUAAGCCUGUGGUCAGGUAGUUGCGUUGGCAGGAUGCCCGUCUGGCUUUGUGCUCCGGAGGGCACAUUACCACCAGGUGCAGGGAUCUCUGCUUGCUUUGGUCUGUUCACAGACACAAGCUGCCUUUUCUGGUUCUUGCGUGCACUCCUUGGUUUCUUAAGUUCAGCUAUAGGUAUAUAUUUUUUUCUUUCAGGCUCACUUCCUGCCUCCAUUAUCCUGUACCGCAUAUUGUAUCUGUUGGUUGAGUAGAGAGAGAUUCAUCCAGAGUCAUCAGCGCUCCAAUAGUCCUUUAUCAGAUUAAGGACUUGAGGGAAAUGUGCAUUAUGCUUUAGUAGGCACUCUAAAAGUUCCUUGAAUUGGAUUCUUCUUUCCAUACUUAUGUUCUGAGUACUAACUUUGUUUUAAACUUCUGCGCCAAAAGUUGGCUUUUCUGAACUCUGCAUUUUCAAACUCUUCCCUUCUGUUAUUUGAAAAUCAGAUAAGUCAACUCAUUGUAAGAUGGAUAAUUUCUUUACUCACGCCGUGAUGAAAUAAUGCGAUUAUAGUACUCUGUACAAUGGUACAUAUGGUACUUGCACAUAUGGUCAGUUAACAAAAACUGCCCCUUCUUUCUUUACUGUGUUAGUCUCAUCCUCUUAAUGUUGCUGCGGUUAACAUUCUCGAUCUUAACUUCGCGGAUCUAACACAGUGUCCUUUAAAAAAGGCCUUUAUCUACAUGAAUUGUAUAUAAAUAUCCACCUCCGUUUUCUUCUAGUAUUGUUAAUGAUCUUAUUUAUAUUUAAUGUGAGAUAAGAAGGCUCUAACUUUAUAAUUUUGUUAGUGACUCCAUCAUCAUUUGUUGGAAUUCUAUUUUUCCCUGCUGAUCAGUCCUAUAAAUACCAUAGGCCCUAAAUUCCCGUGUAUUCUUGGGACUUUCUGAACGGUCUAGUAUUCUUUGGCUCCCUGUGGUGAUCCUGGCUUCUGUGAUGCUCUUAUUGCUCUAGGUUUAUAAUGUGUUUUAAUAUCUAGGGAUUUGAACGAUGCCUGGCAUAUUGUAGACAUCACUAAAUAUUUUUGAAAUGAACACAUUUAGUGGGGGCAAGUUGAUUCCCUUUCUUUACCUCUUGCCUCCCUCCCCCCUUUAAAAUUUUCCUGCCAGUUAUUGAGAUUCAUUUAUUUUAGCUUGCUUUUUCCAUGGUCAGUUGAAUCAUUAACUGUUAGUAAAUAAAUCCCUUCUGUUGCUCAUUCAGAACUUGCGACUAGAGUUGCUCCUUACAGUUACAUAGAGAAGCAGCCUGAUUAAAAAUCUGCAUGCCUUUUGACUUUGCACCGUGUCAUAGUAACUGUAGUGUGUCUCUCCCCAUCACCUGUGAUUUAGGAUGUUCUGUACCUGGUUUCUAAGAGAAAAAUGGUUAUCUAAGAGAUAAAUGGCUGUAGAAGUGUUCCCUGGGAUAUGAGGAAGAUAUCCUCAUAUCCAUUUGUAUUUUACCAUCACAACUGGAUAUCUAAAAUAUAAUAAAUUUUACACUGGACACUUAAAACUUUAUUAGCCCAUGAAAUAAAUGUAUGCAUUCUUUAAAAAAGAUCAAGCAAUACAGAAAUCCUUAAAGGAGGAAGUGAAAGUGCUGUGUGCCCACCUACCCAGUAACCUUGUUCCAUAAAGAUGAUCACUGCUUGCAGAUUUUAAAAAUAAAUAUAUUUAAGUCUACUUUUGUUUCAUAAAUGGCAGUGUACCAUCUAUAAUUUUCUAUAGCUUCCACUUAAUAAUAAUUGAUAAACAUCCUUCUGUGUCAGUGCAUAUAAUAGUAUCUUGUCUUUUUUGUAAGUCUUUUGGUAUUUCAUUGUAGGAAUAACCCAAAAGUUAUUUAGCCAGUCCCCUGUUGGCAUUAUUCCAAAUUUAUUACAAACAGAACUGCAAGGAUCAUUUUUGUGUUUAUUCUGUAUACUGUCAUGUUUGCAUGUUAGUUCAUUUCCUAAGAUAUGGAAUUGCUAGGUCAGAGGCUACACAUAAGUGUUAAAUUAUGAGAGAUUCUGCCAAAGUGCUCCUCAAAAGUUGUUGGUAAGAGUAAAUUUAUACAAUUUGUUAAAAUAUUGCUUUUGCCAUAUCACAUUGCCAAGAAUUGUCAAGGAUCUGAGAUCAUACCCUACUUGCAAGCUAACAGUUUCAUGGAAACUGGCAGAAAAUAUGAGACUCCUGACUCAGAGACAAAGCACAACAGGAACGGUAGCCAGAGGAUCAUCUUAUGCUGAUUUGCUGGAACCCUGAUUUCCACAGGGUGAUGUGAUAAGAGCCCAGUGACACUAGCAGAUGAAGUAGGUUAUGUUACAGGAGAGGAGUCCUUAGUUUAGGGAACCUGAAUCUUUCAUAGUGGGCUGCAAAUAAAGCUGUCUGAUCUUUGCCAGAGAGGGAGACAUUAUCUUUAUUUUCCCACAUGGUAAACAAACCUGCCCUCUGUACCAGAGGGAGACAUCUCUUUAUCUGCCAAGGCUAUUUGCUAUAUAAACACCACUGAAAAGAUAAAAAAUAAAGGCCGUCAGUGCCUCUACUUAUAUGAUAUGCAGAAACUUGAGAGGCCUGCUAAGAUGAAAUGAUUAUUUUUUAUAUUUAGUAAUUUUAUGGAUGAAAAAUGCUAUUUUAUUGUUUUAGUAUUGCAUUUCUUUGCUUAUUGAUGAGGUUGACUAUCUGUAUGUUUGUUGGUCAUUUGUAUUCGUUUUUACUUGCAUGAUCAUAUCCCUUGCUUAGGUUUCUGUUGAAAUGUUCCUCUUUUCUAAUUGAUUUGUAAUAGCUCUUUACAUAUUGUGGCUAUUAAUGAUUUGGUUCACCAUUUGCUAGUAUUUUCUCAUAGUCUAUUCUUUAGUGUUUCUUGGGGCUUUUGCUUUAUAAAAAUCUUUAAUAUUUAUGUUGCCAGUUCUGCUGUUGUUUUCCUUUACGGCCUCUGGGUUUCCACCGGAAGAUUAUUAAAAUACUCUUUGUACACAUUCUGUUAUCAUAGAUAUAGAUUUUUAAAAAUGGUUGCUAUGGCAUACUAUUACAAAUUUAUUUUUCCAAAUUGCUGGACAUUUUCCUAAAACAUUUAUUUUGAUAAACUGUCCUUUCCCUGUUAUUUGAUUUGACACAUUUGUUGUAAGAUACUAUAUCCUUAAUUUGUUGUUUUUCUCAAAGCCAACAAAUUAGUAAGCAAAGUAUGUUAGAUGUUUACUGUGAUUAUGAUUUUGGUUGAAUUCAGCCUUAAAGAUAAUAUGUGUAAUUGUUCUUAGUGGAUUUUAUCUUAAAGAAUAUGAAGUAUCUUUUUUGCCCUGUUUAGUGAUUUUUUGGCUGGGAGUCUACAUUGUCUUAUAUGACUUUUGCCUCUCUGUCAGUUUUGUGUGUACCUGAUAGGUCUUUUUUGUCCAUAUGUUUAUUAUGUUUAUUUUCAGUCAUUUUACACCAUUUUGCUUUACUUGCCUUUCAUAAACAUCAAACAUUCAUGUAACUGAGCUGAACUUUUAUUUCUCCCUGAAAUCUUCCCCCUUGCCAAUUUGGAAGUUUGUCUUCUUUUUUUUUUUUUUUUUUUUUGAGACAGAGUCUUGCUCUGUCACCCAUGCUGGAGUGCAGUGGUGUAAUGUGUAAUUUUGGCUCACUGCAACCUCCAUCUCCUGGACUUAAGUGAUCCUCCUGCCUCAGCCUCUCAAGUAGCCUGGACUGCAGGUGCAUGCCACAAUACCUGGCUAAUUUUUGUGUUUUUUGUAGAGAUGGGGCUUCACCAUGUUGCCCAGGCUGGUCUCAAACUCCUGGGCUCAAGUGAUCCACCCGCCUUGGCCUCCCAACGUGCUGGGGUUACAGGUGUGAGCCACUGUGCCCGGCCUGGAAUUUUGUCCUUUUUUUUUUUGUUUUACAUUUUAUAAAACUUUUAAAAAAGAUCAUUGUAGAUUCAUAUACAGUUGUAAGAAAUAAUACAGAGAUCUAGAUCCUGUGUACAUUCACCCAGUUUCCACCUAUGGUAACACCUUGCAUAACUACAGUACAAUAUUAUACUCAGGAAAUUGACAUUGAUACAAUCUAUAGACCUUAUUCAGAUUUCACCAGUUUUACUUGUACCCAUCCCUGUGCCUGUUUAGUUGUAAGUAAUUUUAUGUAGAUUCCUGUGAACACUACCACAGUCAGAAUAUACAACAGUUCCAUCACAAGGUUACCUUGUACAAAAUUGGGUUUAUCUCUUAAUAGGACAAUUUAAUCUAGUCAUAUUAACUAUUUUUUCCCCUCUCCUGCAAGUUUGGAAAUUCUGAAACCAUCUAUAACUGACUCUUUUUUGCCCUCAUUCUUCCCAUUAAUAAGUUGAGACCUGGAUCUCUUGCCUUCUUUACAUUCUUGGUUUUAUUGAUUUGAUUUCUUUUCUAUAGUUGUAAUAUUCUGUUCCCACAUUGCUAUAAAGAAAUACCUGAGACUGGGUAAUUUAUAAAGUAAAGAGGUUUAAUUGGCUCACAGUUCCACAGGCUGUACAGGAAGCAUGGUGCUGUCAUCUGCUAGGCUUCUGCGAGGCCUCAGGAAAUUUACAAUCAUUGUGGCAGGCAAAGCAGGAGCAAGGGUCUUACAUGGCAGGAGCAGAAGGAAGAGAGUGGGGGAUGCGCUAUAUGCUUUGAAACAAAAAGAUCUCUUCAGAACUCAUAUGAGAACACCACUAGGGGCAUAGUGCUAAACCAUGAGAAACCACCCCCAUGAUCCAAUCACCUUCCAGGCCCCACCUCCAGCACUGGGGAUUACAUUUCACUGUUAGAUUUUGAUGCAGACACAGAUGCAAACCAUAUCAGUAGUUCUUCUGUUUGUUUGUUUUUUUCUAACCAUUUUUUAAAAUUUUGCUAGUAUCGUAUCACUUAGAUUUAACUAUAAGGUCACUGUUACUUGAAUAGUAUGUCUUCCCUGUUUUUGAAGUAUUUAAUUCUGUUGUUUUUUUUUUUAACUGGCAUACAUUUUUAAGUAAUAGUUUCAGGAAGAGUUAUGGGAAGUAUACUUGCAUAUCUAGAAUAUUUUUUAUUUAAUUUUGUUUUUUCUAUGUGAAUAAGAGUUUGAGCCAUUUUUUUUUUCCUUUAGAAUUUCCUUGAACUUAAAUUAGCUUCAGUCUUUAUCUUAUAUAGAUGUUAGGUUUCUUGUAUAUGUGCUCUAGGUCAUUUAUUUGUCUCUUAAUUUUCAAUUUAUUUCAGUCACCACCUCUUCUAAGAAUUUUUUUAAGUUAGUUUGUGCUUAUUUCAUGGAUCCUAUAACCUAUUAAUUAACACUAAACAAUGAUUUUUAAAAAAAACUAUUGUCCUAAUUUUGGCUUUAACUUUUCCUGAAUGCCAUUUGCUGUAAUUGCUUAACUUGUUUCCCUGUCUUUAAAAUGGUUAAUUCUAUUCAGACAUAUAAAUGCAGAUCUAUGUUGACCAUCUUGGUCCUGGUCUGAAGUAUUUCAUGUCAUGAAGGUCACUAUUCUGUUUUCCAGACAGGUAGUUUCCUAAGGCAAGAUGAGUGGUUGGGGCUGUGUGAGCAGGCUUUGCCCUGGGCAGAACAAGUGGGCAGAACAUGCCAACUAGUAGAUAUCUUUAAAGAGAACAGACAAGUAAGCUAGCGUGUGCAUAACCAAAUCAAUACUAGAGUAUCGGAUUUACAGCUUGACUUGUUUUGACUGAAAACAAAAGCACACAGAACAGUUACAUCAUCCUAAAAAUUCCUUGUGUGGCCCCUUUGUGGUUACUUUAGUCAAUUUCUCUUUCUUCCCUUAACCCUGGGCAAUCACUGAUUUAUCUGCCUUUCCUAUUUGCCUUUUCCAAAGUAUCACAUAAAUGAAAUCAUACAAUAUGUAGUUUUUGCAUCAGACCUCUGUCACUUAACAAAAUGCAUUUUAAGAUUCAUCUAUAUUAUUGCCUGGAUUGGUGGUUCUUUCUUUUUUUUUUUCCUGAGUAGUAACUCAUUGUAUGGAUGUAACACUGUACAUGCAUCUGUCAAGGACAUCUUAGAUGUUUCCAAGUUGCAACAAUUAUGAAUAAAUCUGCUAUAAACAUUUGUAUACAGGUUUUUGGUUGGAUGUAGGUUUUCAGUACACUUGAGUAAAUACCUCGGAAUGGGAUUGCUGGAUGGUUUGGUAAGGGCGGAUGGACCUUUAUAAUAAACCGUGAAACUGUUUUUCAAAGUGGCUAUAUGAUUUUGCAUUCCCACUAGAAAUGUUUGCAGAAUCUAAUUUGGUAUCUUAAAAUUUGAUUAAUUUGUAGUUAACUCUUCCCAGGUCUUCCCUUAAGAGCAAAUACUUCCCAGGUCUAAGAUGAAAUACUUUCUCAGGGUUUACUCUUUUGAAACUGUACUUGAUCUUGCUCUUCGGUAAUAUGUUUGCUAGGACAUGUACAAGUAUCCCAUAAGAGAAAAAAAGAUAUUUUCAAGUAGAUGAAAAGGCAAGCACAGACUGGGAGAAAACAUUUGCAAAAACAUCUGUCUAACAAAGAAAUUGUAUCUAGUGUGUGUAAAGAACUCUUACAACUCCAUAGUAAGGAAACAACAACAAAAAAAAGAUUAGAAAAUAGACACUGCACUAAAGAAGAUAUAAAUGGCAAAUAAGCACGUGAAAAGAUGUUCCAUGUCAUUAAUCAAUUAAGAAAUUCAAAUUAAAACCACAGGGUAUCACCACCCACCCACUAGAAUGGAUGAAGAUUGACAAUAUUAACUAUUGAUGAGGAUGUGGAGCAACUGGAACUCUCAUAUGUUGAUGUCAGAAUGUAAAAUGCUACAGCCACUUUGGAAAUGGCUUGAUACUAGAAACAAGCCAAAUGUUUAGCAACAACUGAAUUGAUAUACCAAUGUAGCUGACCCUUGAACAACAUGGGUUUGGACUGUGAAGAUAUGCUUAUAUGCAGUUUUUUUCAAUAAAUAUAGAAAAAUUUUGGAGAUUUGCAACAAUUUGAAAAACUUGCAAAUUGUGUAGCCUAGAAAUAUCAAAAAAAGGUAUUUCACAAAUAAAUAAAAUAUAUGUAGAUACUAGUCUAUUUUAUAAUUUACUGCCAUGAAUAGCACACAUAUAUAUUAUAAAAAAUUAAACUUUUUCAAAAGGUAGUCACACACUUACAGAAUGUACAUGCUUCCAUUUGCAGUUCAGAGAAAUGUAAACAAAUGUAAAUUCAGUAUUAAAUCAUAACUGCAUAAAAUUAGCUGUGGUACAUACUGUACUACUGUAAUAAUUUGAUGAUCACCUCCAGUUACUAUUGCAGUGAGCUUAAAUAUUGCAGGUAUCAGCUUCCAAUGCUGUGUGAAGCUAAUCAUCGACACAUGAGCAGUUUGUCUCUAGUAAAUUGUGUAUUACAGUAAGAAGUGAUUUCUUGUGAUUCUCACGUAUUUUUCAUCAUGCUUAGUGUAAUACCAUAAACUUUGAAUAACACCAUGGGACCCUUAGAAAGUGCCACUGGUAAUGUCGGAAGUGAUUCCAAGUAGCAGCGAGAAGUCAUGACAUUACAAGCAAAAAUGGAAUUGCUUGUUAUGUACCAUAGAUUACAGUCUGCAGCUAUGGUUACCUGUCAUUUCAAGAUAAACGAAUCCAGCAAAAGGACCACUGUGAAAAAAGAAAAGAGAAUUUAUGUAGCUGUUGCUACAACUAUACCAGCAGGUGCAAAACCUUGCACUUUUUGUGAAAUACCACUUUAUCUCAUAUUGAAAAUGCAGUUCUUAUGUGGGUGCAGGAUUGCUAUAAGAAAGACAUGCUUGUAGACUCUAAUAUGAUUUGAGAGAAAGUGAAGUUAAUGUAUGACAGCUUAAAGCAAAAAGAAGGUGAAGGAUAGAAAGCUAGAGAAUUUAAUGCCAGCAAAGGAUGGUUUGAUAAUUGUAGAAAGAAGUUUGGCUUUAUGUAUGUUAAGAUAACAGGAAAGCAGCUGCUACUGUUCAAGAGGCAGCAGAUGAUUUCCCAGAUACCAUUAAAAUAAUUGAGGAGAAAGGAUAUCUGCUUAAAUGGGAUUCUUUCUCUCUCUCAUUUCAUUUCGUUUCGUUUCAUUUCAUCUCCCUUCCUCCCUCCCUCCUGUCUUGUCUUUUCCUUUCUCUUCUCUUUUUUUUUUUUUUUUUUUUUUUUUUUGAGACAAGGUCUUGCUCUGUCACCCAGGCUGAAGUGCAAUGGCAUGAUCACAGCUUACUGUAGCCCCAGCCUCCUGAGGUGGAAACAGUCCUCCCAAAUAGCUAGGAUUACAGGUGCACACCACCACACUUAGCUAAUUUUUUAUUUUUUAUUUUUGUAGAGGCAGGGUCUCCCUAUGUUUCUUAGGCUGGUCUUAAACUCCUGGUCUCCAGUGAUCCUUCUGCCUUGGCCUCCCAAAGUACUGGGAUUACAGGCAUGAGCCGCUGUGCCCAGCCUCAGUCAGGUUUUGAAUGCAGACAAAGUGCCCUAUUCUGGAAAAAAAAAAUGCCACAAAAGACAUUUAUUAUUAAAGAAGUAAAGCAAGCACCAGGAUUUAAGGCAGGAAGGGAUAGACUAACUCUGGUGUUUUGUGCAAAUGUAUCUGGGUUUAUGAUCAAGACUGCUUAUUUAUAAAGCUACUAACCCCCAGCCUUAAAGGGAAAAGGUAAAUGCCAGUUAUCAGUCUUUUCGUUAUGUAACAGGAAGGCCUGGACAAUCAGAGUUCUUUUUCUUGAUUGAUUUCAUCAAUGCUUUGUCCCUGAAGUCAGGAAGUAUUAAUACCUUGCUAUAAGGGACUGCCUUUUAAAGUUCUUUUGGUAUCAGACAAUGUCCCUGGCCACCCAGAACUCCACGAGUUUAACACUGAAGGUGUCGAAGUAUAUUCCACAUGUCCCCAAAUGCAAUGUCCCUAAUUCAGCCUCCAGAUCAGGGGGUUGUAAGGAACUUUAAGGCUUACUAUACAUGGUACUCUAUGGAAAGAACUGUGAACUCUAUGGAUGAGAACCUCAACAGAGAGAACCUGUAAGUUUGGAAGGAUUACACCAUUGAAUAUGCCAUUGUUACAGAAAAAACUGUGAAGGCCAUCAAGACUCAAACAAUAAGAAAACUAAAGAAAACUCUACCAAUAGUGUACAUGACUUCACAGGAUAUAUGACAGAACCAAUCAAGGAAAUCAUGAAAGAGAUUGUAGAUAGGGCAAAAAAAAAAAAAAAAAAGGGUGCAGGGGGAGGAGGAUGAAGGGUUUCAAGAUAUGGAUCUUAGAGAAAUUCAAGAGCUAAUAGACUCCACACCAAAGGAGUUAACAGAAAACAACUUGGUGGAGACGAGUGUUUCUGAAUUAGUGCCAGAUGACGAGGAAGAAGACAUAAAAGAGGCAGUGCCAGAAAACAAAUUGACAUUAGACAAUUUGGCAGAAAGUUCCAAUUAUUCUGGACAGUUUUGACUUCUUUUACAACAUGGACCCUUCUAUGACAUGGACACUGAAACUAAAGCAAAUGGUGGAAGAAGGAUUGGUACUGUAUAGAGAUAUUUUUGGAGAAAUGAAAUAGCAAAAAGUCAGGCAGAAUUUAUAGUAUAUUUCCACAAAAUUGCACCGAGUGUGCCUGCCUCUCCUGCCUCUUUUUACACCUCCUCCAUCACUUUCACCCUGUAUCCUGAAAUGGCAAGGACCACCCCUCCUCUUCCUCCUCCCUUCUCAGCCUACUCAACAUGAAGAUCAGAUCGAAGACCUUUGUGGUGAUUCACUUUCACUUAAUGAGUAGUCAAUAUAUUUUCUCUUCCUUAUGAUUUUGUUAACAGUACUUUUCUCUAGCUUACUUUAUUAUAAGCAUAAAUUAUAUAACUUACAAAAUAUGUUAAUCAACUGUUUAUGUUAUUGGUAAGCCUUCUGGUCGACAGUAGCCUAUUAGUAAAGUUUUGGGUGAGUCAAAAGUUAUAUUCAGAUUUUUUUUUUUUUUUGAGACGAAGUCACCCAGGCUGGAGUGCAGUGGCACAAUCUCGGCUCACUGCAACCUCUGCCUCCCAGGUUCAAGUGAUUCUCCUGCCUCAGCCUCCUGAGUAGUUGGGAUUAUAGGUGUGUGCCACCACAACUGUUUAAUUUUUGUAUUUUUAGUAGAGACAGGGUUUUUCCCUAUUGGCCAGGCUGGUCUCAAACUCCUGACCUCUGGUGAUCCACCUGCCUCAGUUUCCCAAAAUGCUGGGAUUACAGGCAUGAGCCACUAUUCCAGCCUAUAUUCAGAUUUUUUUACUGCAUAGGGGGUCAGUGCCCCAAUCCCAUACAUUGUUCAAGGGUCAACUGUAUAAUGGGAUUUGAUUCAGAAUAAAAAGGAACUGAACUACUCUUAACACAUAGCAUCAUGGGUAAAUCUGGAAGAUAGACUGAACAAAAUAAGCUAGACACAAAAUAAUACAGUUGAUCCUCAAACAACAUGAAGGUUAGGGGUGCCAAUCCCCCAUGCAGUUGAUCCAGCUAUAAUUUUUUACUCCCCAUAAGCUUAACUACCACUGAAUAGCCUAUGGUUGACUGGAAGCCUUACUGAUAACAUAUACAGUUGGUUAAUAUAUGUUUUAUAUGUUAUAUGUAUUGUAUACUGUAUUCUUACAAUGAAAUAGGCUAGAGAAAGAAAAUAUUAAGAAAAUCAUGAGGAAAAGAAAAUAUAUUUACUCCUCAUUAAGUGGAAAUAGGUCAUCAUAAAGGUAUUCAUCCUCAUUGUCGUCAUGUUAAAUAGACUAAGAGGGAGGAAGAGGAUGGGUCAGUCUUGCUGUUUCAGAGAUCGCAGAGACAGAAGAAAAGGCACAUAUAAGUGGACCCACACAGUUCAAACCUGUGUUAAGGGUUAGCCAUACAUACCAUAUUAUUUCACUUUCAUAUAAUUCUGGAAUAAAGGACAAUCUGGUUUGUAGUGACAGAAAGCAGAUCAGUUUUUGCUUGGCAUAGGUUGUGGAUGGGUGAUUGACCAGGGAUCCUUUUAGGCUAGUGGUAAUAUUCUGUAUCUUGAUUUUGGUGGUGGUUAUGUUGGUUUCUGUCAUUGUCAAAACUCAUCAAAUUAUAUGCUUAAAGUGGGGUACAUUUUAUACUAAAGUUAAUUUAACAGUAUUACACCAUUUUAAUUAGUUGCUAUUUUAGCUAUAAUGGCAAGCUAUGACAGGUGUAUUGUCCUUGGAUUUUUGUUUGGCAGGGUGUAAAUCCACUAUAUUUUUUUCUAGGUAAAAUGUUCUCUAUGUUAAUGUACAAAAAUAUAUGGCUAGUAUUUGGCUAAAGUAAAUUCACAUAAUUAGUAUGACUUUAACAAACAAAAUAUCAUUUUUUCUUUCUUCAGUAAGUUCCUUAAAUUUAUCCUCAGCCAGAUAUCUCCAAUUUUUAAUAUUUUAGUUAAAUAUCAUUGCAUAUCUGCUAAAGAUUUAGGGUUAUUCCAGAGUCACAGUUCUUCUCAUUCAGAUGCCUUAUUCUUUUUUUUUUUUUGAGACGGAGUCUCGCUCUGUCGCCCAGGCCAGACUGCGGACUGCAGUGGCGCAAUCUCGGCUCACUGCAAGCUCCGCUUCCCGGGUUCACGCCAUUCUCCUGCCUCAGCCUCCCGAGUAGCUGGGACUACAGGCGCCCGCCACCGCGCCCGGCUAAUUUUUUGUAUUUUUAGUAGAGACGGGGUUUCACCUUGUUAGCCAGGAUGGUCUCGAUCUCCUGACCUCAUGAUCCACCCGCCUCGGCCUCCCAAAGUGCUGGGAUUACAGGCGUGAGCCACCGCGCCCGGCCCAGAUGGCUUAUUCUUACCCAUCGUUAAACACUGAAGAAAAAGGUAAUAUAUAGGUAAUAUAACAGUGGAAUCUAUUUCUAAGUUAUGUUGUAUCAUCGUACCUGUGUAAUUAGAAACAUAUCCUUUCUUUUCACUUUGUGAGAUAGCAUGUUGGGCAGGAAGAGGGUUUCCAGAUCCAUUAUAUCAGAAAAAAAAAAAACAAAAAACCAUUCCACUCAUCCUAUAGCUCUACUUAAAAAAAAAAAAAAGAUUCCUUCAGUUCCUUUUUCUGCUUUUCUUGCUACUAAAGAUUGAUUAUGAAAUAUUUCAGAAGUUUAGAUAUGCUUGUUAAAGAAAGUCUAGGAAAGAAAGAACAUAUUCUGCAGAAGUAACCUUUCUCAAUUCCUAGUUUAAAUUGGUUCUAAAUCUUAUCUCUUGUUUUCUGAUAAAUUCAUUCCUACUUGACUUCUUGGGUACCUCUUGCUUAGUUCCUGCCCUUUAUUCAUUAACUCACCAGAGGUUUUUGCACAGUCUAAUGUAUUCCAGACUUUUUGGAUUAUUUCCUUGCAUUUUUGAGAUCUACCUUGAUUCCUCGAAGAGAGUGGUACUGUUUACCUCUGGUUUUUGAGAUUUUUGCUCUGCUUUUAGAUUUUUCUUCCUGGCCUGGUUCCCUUGCCUUCUCCAUUUGCUUCAUUCGCUUGGAUUUUCAAGAAGCUUUGAAGCUGGAUAGGAGUCUCCAGUCUUCCUCUUGAUCCAUAUGUUUCAGGUAAAAGAAUGUCACAUGUCAGCAUUUGUACCUGAAGUCAGCAUGCAAAGUUCAGGGUACCUGGAUGAAUGCCAACUUUUGCAUUUCCCAUGUGUAUCCUGUGACCAUUCUAUCUGGGAACAUCCUUCAAAGAGUUCAUGCAUCUUACUGAGGACACCUGACCUUUUGAAGCUUCAUAAUUCACAUCUAGAUGUCACCGGUCUUUCCCAUGUUAACAGUUCUGACCAUGUUUUAUUAUAUAUGCCUUCGGCGCCGAGCCAGGACAGCUACAAGAGGAGAAAUGAUGAACACCCAUAGAGCUAUAGAAUCAAACAGCCAGACUUCCCCUCUCAAUGCAGAGGUAGUCCAGUAUGCCAAAGAAGUAGUGGAUUUCAGUUCCCAUUAUGGAAGUGAGAAUAGUAUGUCCUAUACUAUGUGGAAUUUGGCUGGUGUACCAAAUGUAUUCCCAAGUUCUGGUGACUUUACUCAGACAGCUGUGUUUCGAACUUAUGGGACAUGGUGGGAUCAGUGUCCUAGUGCUUCCUUGCCAUUCAAGAGGACGCCACCUAAUUUUCAGAGCCAGGACUAUGUGGAACUUACUUUUGAACAACAGGUGUAUCCUACAGCUGUACAUGUUCUAGAAACCUAUCAUCCCGGAGCAGUCAUUAGAAUUCUCGCUUGUUCUGCAAAUCCUUAUUCCCCAAAUCCACCAGCUGAAGUAAGAUGGGAGAUUCUUUGGUCAGAGAGACCUACGAAGGUGAAUGCUUCCCAAGCUCGCCAGUUUAAACCUUGUAUUAAGCAGAUAAAUUUCCCCACAAAUCUUAUACGACUGGAAGUAAAUAGUUCUCUUCUGGAAUAUUACACUGAAUUAGAUGCAGUUGUGCUACAUGGUGUGAAGGACAAGCCAGUGCUUUCUCUCAAGACUUCACUUAUUGACAUGAAUGAUAUAGAAGAUGAUGCCUAUGCAGAAAAGGAUGGUUGUGGAAUGGACAGUCUUAACAAAAAGUUUAGCAGUGCUGUCCUCGGGGAAGGGCCAAAUAAUGGGUAUUUUGAUAAACUACCUUAUGAGCUUAUUCAGCUGAUUCUGAAUCAUCUUACACUACCAGACCUGUGUAGAUUAGCACAGACUUGCAAACUACUGAGCCAGCAUUGCUGUGAUCCUCUGCAAUACAUCCACCUCAAUCUGCAACCAUACUGGGCAAAACUAGAUGACACUUCUCUGGAAUUUCUACAGUCUCGCUGCACUCUUGUCCAGUGGCUUAAUUUAUCUUGGACUGGCAAUAGAGGCUUCAUCUCUGUUGCAGGAUUUAGCAGGUUUCUGAAGGUUUGUGGAUCCGAAUUAGUACGCCUUGAAUUGUCUUGCAGCCACUUUCUUAAUGAAACUUGCUUAGAAGUUAUUUCUGAGAUGUGUCCAAAUCUACAGGCCUUAAAUCUCUCCUCCUGUGAUAAGCUACCACCUCAAGCUUUCAACCACAUUGCCAAGUUAUGCAGCCUUAAACGACUUGUUCUCUAUCGAACAAAAGUAGAGCAAACAGCACUGCUCAGCAUUUUGAACUUCUGUUCAGAGCUUCAGCACCUCAGUUUAGGCAGUUGUGUCAUGAUUGAAGACUAUGAUGUGAUAGCUAGCAUGAUAGGAGCCAAGUGUAAAAAACUCCGGACCCUGGAUCUGUGGAGAUGUAAGAAUAUUACUGAGAAUGGAAUAGCAGAACUGGCUUCUGGGUGUCCACUACUGGAGGAGCUUGACCUUGGCUGGUGCCCAACUCUGCAGAGCAGCACCGGGUGCUUCACCAGACUGGCACACCAGCUCCCAAACUUGCAAAAACUCUUUCUUACAGCUAAUAGAUCUGUGUGUGACACAGACAUUGAUGAAUUGGCAUGUAAUUGUACCAGGUUACAGCAGCUGGACAUAUUAGGAACAAGAAUGGUAAGUCCGGCAUCCUUAAGAAAACUCCUGGAAUCUUGUAAAGAUCUUUCUUUACUUGAUGUGUCCUUCUGUUCGCAGAUUGAUAACAGAGCUGUGCUAGAACUGAAUGCAAGCUUUCCAAAAGUGUUCAUAAAAAAGAGCUUUACUCAGUGACUUAAUAUAUGUUCUGUAUUAAAAUUAAUGUGCUUUGUUGGGGUUUAAUUUUGGGAUUGGUUUUGGGUUUUGUUUUUAGUUGUUUUAAUGGUAAGAAUUAAGACAUUUGUAGAUUUUAAAGAAAAAUAUGAAAUUGUCCAUUAAAUCAAGUAAAAAUGUGCACAAAUGUUUUCAUAAAAUACUGCAAGCACUUCUCUUCAAGAAUAUGAGUGGAUAUUAUUUUUACCUUAUGUUAAUCAGUGAUAUGCUUUAGUCAAUAAUAUGAUUGAUAAAAGAAUAACAUGGAAUCAUGCUAACUUAUUUUCAAAGGAACACUGAGCAAUAAAGUAUCGUGGCAUUUAUGCAAAAAAAAAAGUUAAUUUUUUACACCUUCAUGUAAGGAUGUCUUAUUAAGCCUGUGACCUGGCAAGUGUUUUGUUUGGUAUGUACAAAAUGGUCAGAGCUAGUUGGAGAAUGAGACAUGCUUUUCCAGCUGUUUGGUUAUUUCUCUGGAUUAACUGUUCAACUGGAAAAUUUUUAGUUUUUCUAGCCAGGUGUGGUGGCACACACUUGUAGUCCUAGCGACACAGGAGGUGGAGGCAGGAGGAUUACUUGAGAUGGGAUUUUGAGACUCUAGUGUACUUAUGAUUGCACCUGUGAGCAGCCACUGCACUCCAACCUGGGCAAUAUAGCAAGUCCCUUUCUCUUAAAAAAAAUUGUAGUGUUUCCACUUUUCUUCUGAUAUUUUUGUCUAUUUCACUACUGGAUAAUGCCAAUAUAAAAAUUUGGGUAUAAUCAAGAAUAAGAGGUAAACUACUAAAUAAAAAAAGCUUUCCAACUGUUAGAAGCAGAUGCCUUAACAUUUUGUGAAAGGUAAAGUUUUGAGGUUUCUGAAUUAUAUAAAAAAACAUAAAUGUGGAGAUAUAUAUUAUAUAUACACAUUAUAUAUACAUAUUAUAGAUAAUAUAUAUCCACAUUUAUGAUUUUUAAUAUAUACAUGUAUAUAUUAUAUAUUAUAUAAUUAUAUAUUACAUUUAUAUUAUAUGUAAUGUACAUGUAUAUAUUAUAUACAUAUAUAUAAUUAUAUAUAUUAUAUAGAGAGAGAUAUAUAUCUUGCUAGGGUGUGUGGAUGCUGGAAUAUAACGAUUUUGCACUUAACAGGACAAUGAAUUUUGUUAUACUACAGUUAAUAUUAGUUUUGUGUUCAAAACAGCUGUGCCUUUUCAUGCCACAAAAUAUUUUCUGUCUACUUUCUGAGUAGCAGAAUUAAUUCAUUUUUUUAACAAAACGAUGUAUGUCAAGUGUUCAGUAGUCACAUGAGGAGAAUGCUUCCUUUGUGCCUGGCACUGUUUCUUGUGCUUUGCAUUGACUAAUUCAAUUCUCACAACAACCCUGUAAGAUAAAUGCCAUUACUUACCCCCAUUUACAGAUGAGGAAACUGAGGCAAAGAAAGAUUGAAGAAUUUAUUUAUGAUCAUACAGCUGCUAGUGGCAGAGCCAACAUAUAAACCCAGGCCAUCUGGCUUCUGAAGCAUUGCAUUAAACCUGUGCUUUUAGGUGUUCAGGGUAGCUUCUGGCUCUAGGGCAGAGGUCAGGAAACUUUUUCUAUAAAGGGCCAGAUAGUAAAUAUUUUAGGCUUUGUGGGCUAAGAGGUAAAACUGAGAUUGUUAUGUAGAUACUUAAAUAACUAGAGAGAAAUAAAAUUUGCACGAAAAUUUUAUUGACAAAAUUCAAAACAAUAAUUUAGAACAAUUUUUUUUGUAAUACGGGUUUACUAAUGAAAAGAAUUAAAUAUUUACAGGGAGGAUCAAAGUUAAUGUUUCGUGUCAUUAAAGUUGAUUGUAAGUACUCAUUUGUUAAUGCUGAUCUGUAAUAAGAUUUUAUGUAUUUUACUUCUGAAAAUUCCUUGCAGAUAGGUAUUGUCAAAUACUUACAUUAAUCCAUGAGAAUAUGAUUUUUGUUGAGCAUAUUCAUCACUUGAAAGGUUACUUCUUCUCUGGAUAUUUUCCUUUUAGCAUGUUAUUACAUUGCAGCUUAAUCACUUCCAAUUGAAGACUAGGCAGAAGCUCCUCAAUUGCACUGUUAAAUUGAUUUUGAAAAAUGGAAAUUUCCUUUACAUUUGCAAACUCCAAAAAAUACUGCAGGCACUAUGGUGUGAGCUACAAAUUUGUGUGAGAGUGGAGAUCUCGCUUCUUUGUCUUACCUUUUGAUAGCACAGGAAAUGUGUAAAGCAGCUUGUUGUUACUUGUAAUUCAAACAAUGUUGUCAUCAAAAUGACUUAUGUUUUGCUUGUAAACACGUUUUGCCUUGUAAUUUUGGCUUGAAUUCAUUUCAAAAUUUUAUUAAGUCUUGAGCAAAAGCUAAAUUCCAAAGCCAUUCAGUGUUCCAUAAUAGUGAUUGAGGACAUGUCUUCUUUUUCAGAAAAAUGUCAAUAUCAGCCCUGAACGCAAAAGCUCACAAUAGAACUAACACUAUUAUGCCAAUGUGGUUGGGCAAAUCAGCAUAUUCAUCUUCUGUAUCUGACAAAAGAUAACUGAACCAUUGAUGUUUAAUCUAUCAGAAACUAUGAGAGCAAAUGAAGUUCACCAUUGCUACCAGUAGUUCAGUAAUACAAAAUUGAAUCAAAUAUAUCCCACAAAGUACCUGCUGAUGAAUAAUACAGUAAAUAACCAUAGAUUUUAAAUACCUUCUUACCUUUUCACAGGCUUUAUAAAUUUGACAAACGUAAUCAUUUUGCUUCACACAUUUUUAACACCACCAGUUGUAACACAUCUUAGCAGAUUCUACUUCAGGUUGCAUGAAAUUUGUGUUUUCUUCUUAUAAAAUAUUCAUGCUUGUAAUUGUGCCACACAGAUAAUUCAUAGAGACUAAUUUCAGUCACUUCAACGUUGGCAUUGACUUAUCAAAUAAGCAAUAACUAGGCAGUGUCAGUAACAUCUGUUGACUCAUCAAGAGCCAAGGAAAACCACUCAGGGUCAUUUGCCUUGUUUUUUAUUGACUGUUGAUGUUGUUCCCAGUGUUCUCAAUUCUUUAAGCAACCAUUCUUGCCAAAAGGCUAAUUUAAUAGUCUUAAGUUUACUUUGGACACAGUCCUUCAGCCGAUAGAAUCAAACACAAUUUAGUUAUCGUUAGUAAAAUGUUUUCCUUGCUUGGUUAACAUCUGAGUCACUUUGGCUGCAACUUUAUUUUCAUUUUUGAGUUUGUUUUUUUUUUUUUUUGAGACUGAGUCUCAUUCUUUUGCCCAGGCUGGAGUGCAGUGGCACAAUCUCAGUUCACUGCAACCUCCACCCUGCAGGUUCAAGCGAGUCUCCUGCCUCAGCCUCCCAAGUAGCUGAGAUUACAGGCACAUGCCACCACACCUAACUAAUUUUUAUGUUUUUAGUAGAAAUGGGGUUUUACCAUGUUGUCCAGGCUGGUCUUGAACUCCUGACCUCAAGUGAUCCACCCACUUCAGCCUCCCAAAAUGCUUGGAUUACAGGCAUGAACCACUGCAUCUGACCUCCCUAUAGUAUUCUUUAAGAACAGCUAUAAUGACAUUGCAUAUUAAACAUCAUACUCUGACAUCUAAUCUGAUUUUUAAAAAUUCAUAUACUAAUGUGCCUUAAAAAUGUCACUUCAAGUCUACUUUUCUUUUUUUCUCUUGUUUUGAUGUUAUGGGUAAGCACUAGUAAUAAAAAAUUUAAAAAUAUUGUGGUAUGACAACAUAUGUGGCACUCAAAAUGCUGGUAACUGCAUUACUGCAGUUUUUAGUGUGCCAAGUAGCAGUGCAAAAUGAUGACAGCACCACAUAAGUCUCCUUUGCAUUUGUUCAACUCUGCCAUUCUAAUGUGAAAGCAAUCAUAGACAGUACCUAAACGAAUGAGUGUGGCCAUGUUCCAAUAAAAUUUCAUGAGCACUGAAAGUUGAAUUUUACAUAAUUUUGAUGUGUUACAAAAUACUACUGUGUUAGCCAUUAGAUUUUUUCAGCCAUUAGAAAAUGUGAAACUGUUCUUAUGAGCUGGCUGGAUUUGGCUUGUGGACCAAAUUUGUGACCCCUAUUCCAGAGUAUUUUCGAGUCAGUUAAUCCAUGUUUGCCCAUUCCUAAUUUUAUAAACCACAUUCAAACCUGUUAAUUCGCUGUUAUCAUUCUCAUUUUGCCAUUUAGAUUUUAAAAUGAAGAGCAGUGUUUUGUUAGAAAAAACAAAAUGUUUACCAUAACAAGAAAGAUGUGUAGACAAGAAAGAUAUUUAUGUAGACUCUUUGUUUGUUAAAUUUUGAAGCCAGGUGAUGCAUUGUUAGCUUUGACAACUGACUUAAAUUUUUGUAUAAUUAUUUAUCUUUGCAUUUUGCUCAGGUAAAUUAUCUUCCCAGAGUCUAGAAAUAAAGAUAUCCCUGAUCCUGUUUAAGAGCAUAAAUAAUACUCUCAAUGUAAAUUGUUUUGAAAUAAGAUCUUAAAAAUACAAAAUGUAGACAAUUAAUAUUCAGGUGCUUACUUUUGAGCCAAUAUGUAGCAGAGAAAAACUAAUUUCUCUGUGGCAGUAUUUUUAUUUUUGGCAUUUCCCAGGAAUUAACUGAAGACUAAAACUCAUAUGUGAAGUGUAAUGAUACUAAUCAAAGAGUCAGUAAAAUUUCCAUUUGGCUACCAUGUAUGUGUGUAUAUAUUUAUGUAUGUAUGUGUGUGUUACAUAUUUGAGACAGGGUCUCACUCUAUUGCCCCAGGCUGGAGUGCAGUGGCAUGAUCUCAGCUUACUGCAGCCUCAGUCUCCCAGGCUCAAGCGAUCCUCCCACCUCGGCCUCCCGAGUACCUGGGACUACAGACACCACCACACCUGGCUAAUUUUUUUAUUUUUUAUAGAGACACAGUCUUUCCAUGUUGCCUAUGUUGGUCUUGAACUCCUGGGCUCAAAUAAUUUUCCCACCUUGGCCUCCUGUAGUGCUGGGAUUACGGGCAUAAGCCACUGUGUCAGGCCCCAUGUAUGUUAAUAGUGAAUGUUUGGCUUUUCAUUUGUUACUUUCAGCUAUUAAAGGAUACCUAUUACAGACACAGGAAUUUACAUUUUCAAAGUCAUUUUUGACACAUCAGUGCUGCAUCUACUUUUCUCCUUUUAGCACAUUUGAUAUUGAUACUUCAGAGAAACUUUUUUAACUACCCUUAAAAUCUUGUCAAUGACCAUUAACUGCCAAUCAUCACCUCAUUUGCUUUUUUUGACAACAUACUACUAGAAACCUAGGCUGUGAGUGUAAAACCAUAACUGUUAGAAUCAUUUUUUUGGCAAUAGCUCACAUUCUGUUAAGAGUCAUUUGCUUUAAUCAAAGAUCAUGAUUUAUUAUAUAUUUUUUAUAAGUAGGGAUGGGGCCAAGAUUAUUCCUUUGGCACAGCAGUAAGUGUGCUCAAGAUCUUUGCCUGUAAGCUUGAAUAUUUGGCUUAAAUUUUGUGCAUAUGAAUACUGUUAAAGGUAUAUUUGACUACAUUUUGAAAGGAAAAAGGUAGUCCUGCUAAAAUUGACAUUUAGGGAUAUUUUAAUCUAUGUAUUUGGUAAAGUAAUUAGUGAAGUAUUAGUUAUAAAAAUUUUAAGGAAAACAUUUAAAAGCAAAAUAGUCGUAUCAGAUAAAUAGAGUAGAAUACACUAAAGAUAAAACAAGUCUCUGUUACAAAUGAAGUUGUCUGUACAGACGACUGAGAUAUUUUAAUUUUAUUUACAUAAAAAUGCUGUUCAAUAUCUAAUGAUUUCUGUUGUUUGUAUUCUGUACUUUAGAGUAAUAAAAUAAGUUUGAGUAUCUCAUUA